UCUUUCCCAUAUCAGCAGCGACAGCUUCCUGUGUGACUGCCAGCUGAAGUGGCUGCCCCCGUGGCUAAUUGGCAGGAUGCUGCAGGCCUUUGUGACAGCCACCUGUGCCCACCCAGAAUCACUGAAGGGUCAGAGCAUUUUCUCUGUGCCACCAGAGAGUUUCGUGUGCGAUGACUUCCUGAAGCCACAGAUCAUCACCCAGCCAGAAACCACCAUGGCUAUGGUGGGCAAGGACAUCCGGUUUACAUGCUCAGCAGCCAGCAGCAGCAGCUCCCCCAUGACCUUUGCCUGGAAGAAAGACAAUGAAGUCCUGACCAAUGCAGACAUGGAGAACUUUGUCCACGUCCACGCGCAGGACGGGGAAGUGAUGGAGUACACCACCAUCCUGCACCUCCGUCAGGUCACUUUCGGGCACGAGGGCCGCUACCAAUGUGUCAUCACCAACCACUUUGGCUCCACCUAUUCACAUAAGGCCAGGCUCACCGUGAAUGUGUUGCCAUCAUUCACCAAAACGCCCCACGACAUAACCAUCCGGACCACCACCAUGGCCCGCCUCGAAUGUGCUGCCACAGGUCACCCAAACCCUCAGAUUGCCUGGCAGAAGGAUGGAGGCACGGAUUUCCCCGCUGCCCGUGAGCGACGCAUGCAUGUCAUGCCGGAUGACGACGUGUUUUUCAUCACUGAUGUGAAAAUAGAUGACGCAGGGGUUUACAGCUGUACUGCUCAGAACUCAGCCGGUUCUAUUUCAGCUAAUGCCACCCUGACUGUCCUAGAGACCCCAUCCUUGGUGGUCCCCUUGGAAGACCGUGUGGUAUCUGUGGGAGAAACAGUGGCCCUCCAAUGCAAAGCCACGGGGAACCCUCCGCCCCGCAUCACCUGGUUCAAGGGGGACCGCCCGCUGAGCCUCACUGAGCGGCACCACUUGACCCCUGACAACCAGCUCCUGGUGGUUCAGAACGUGGUGGCAGAGGAUGCGGGCCGAUAUACCUGUGAGAUGUCCAACACCCUGGGCACGGAGCGAGCUCACAGCCAGCUGAGCGUCCUGCCCGCAGCAGGCUGCAGGAAGGAUGGGACCACGGUAGGCAUCUUCACCAUUGCUGUCGUGAGCAGCAUCGUCCUGACGUCACUGGUCUGGGUGUGCAUCAUCUACCAGACCAGGAAGAAGAGUGAAGAGUACAGUGUCACCAACACAGAUGAAACCGUCGUGCCACCAGAUGUUCCAAGCUACCUCUCUUCUCAGGGGACCCUUUCUGACCGACAAGAAACCGUGGUCAGGACCGAGGGUGGCCCUCAGGCCAAUGGGCACAUUGAGAGCAAUGGUGUGUGUCCAAGAGAUGCAAGCCACUUUCCAGAGCCCGACACUCACAGCGUUGCCUGCAGGCAGCCAAAGCUCUGUGCUGGGUCUGCGUAUCACAAAGAGCCGUGGAAAGCGAUGGAGAAAGCUGAAGGGACACCUGGGCCACAUAAGAUGGAACACGGUGGCCGGGUCGUAUGCAGUGACUGCAACACCGAAGUGGACUGUUACUCCAGGGGACAAGCCUUCCACCCCCAGCCUGUGUCCAGAGACAGCGCACAGCCAAGUGCGCCAAAUGGCCCGGAGCCGGGUGGGAGUGACCAAGAGCAUUCUCCACAUCACCAGUGCAGCAGGACUGCCGCUGGGUCCUGCCCCGAGUGCCAAGGGUCGCUCUACCCCAGUAACCACGAUAGAAUGCUGACGGCUGUGAAGAAAAAGCCAAUGGCAUCUCUAGAUGGGAAAGGGGAUUCUUCCUGGACUUUAGCAAGGUUGUAUCACCCGGACUCCACAGAGCUACAGCCUGCAUCUUCAUUAACUUCAGGCAGUCCAGAGCGCGCGGAAGCCCAGUACUUGCUUGUUUCCAAUGGCCACCUCCCCAAAGCAUGUGACGCCAGUCCCGAGUCCACGCCACUGACAGGACAGCUCCCCGGGAAACAGAGGGUGCCACUGCUGUUGGCACCAAAAAGCUAGGUUUUGUCUACCUCAGUUCUUGUCAUACCAAUCUCUACGGGAAAGAGAGGUAGGAGAGGCUGCGAGGAAGCUUGGGUUCAAGCGUCACUCAUCUGUACAUAGUUGUAACUCCCAUGUGGAGUAUCAGUCGCUCACAGGACUUGGAUCUGAAGCACAGUAAACGCAAGAGGGGAUUUGUGUACAAAAGGCAAAAAAAGUAUUUGAUAUCAUUGUACAUAAGAGUUUUCAGAGAUUUCAUAUAUAUCUUUUACAGAGGCUAUUUUAAUCUUUAGUGCAUGGUUAACAGAAAAAAAUUAUACAAUUUUGACAAUAUUAUUUUUCGUAUCAGGUUGCUGUUUAAUUUUGGAGGGGGUGGGGAAAUAGUUCUGGUGCCUUAACGCAUGGCUGGAAUUUAUAGAGGCUACAACCACAUUUGUUCACAGGAGUUUUUGGUGCGGGGUGGGAAGGAUGGAAGGCCUUGGAUUUAUAUUGCACUUCAUAGACCCCUAGGCUGCUGUGCGGUGGGACUCCACAUGCGCCGGAAGGAGCUUCAGGUGAGCACUGCUCAUGUGUGGAUGCCCCUGCAACAGGCUUCCCUGUCUGUAGAGCCAGGGGUGCAAGUGCCAUCCACACUUGCAGUGAAUGGCUUUUCCUUUUAGGUUUAAGUCCUGUCUGUCUGUAAGGCGUAGAAUCUGUCCGUCUGUAAGGCGUAGAAUGAGGGUUGUUAAUCCAUCACAAGCAAAAGGUCAGAACAGUUAAACACUGCCUUUCCUCCUCCUCUUAUUUUAUGAUAAAAGCAAAUGUGGCCUUCUCAGUAUCAUUCGAUUGCUAUUUGAGACUUUUAAAUUAAGGUAAAGGCUGCUGGUGUUGGUACCUGUGGAUUUUUCUAUACUGAUGUUUUCGUUUUGCCAAUAUAAUGAGUAUUACAUUGGCCUUGGGGGACAGAAAGGAGGAAGUUCUGACUUUUCAGGGCUACCUUAUUUCUACUAAGGACCCAGAGCAGGCCUGUCCAUGCCAUUCCUUCGCACAGAUGAAACUGAGCUGGGACUGGAAAGGACAGCCCUUGACCUGGGUUCUGGGUAUAAUUUGCACUUUUGAGACUGGUAGCUAACCAUCUUAUGAGUGCCAAUGUGUCAUUUAGUAAAACUUAAAUAGAAACAAGGUCCUUCAAAUGUUCCUUUGGCCAAAAGCUGAAGGGAGUUACUGAGAAAAUAGUUAACAAUUACUGUCAGGUGUCAUCACUGUUCAAAAGGUAAGCACAUUUAGAAUUUUGUUCUUGACAGUUAACUGACUAAUCUUACUUCCACAAAAUAUGUGAAUUUGCUGCUUCUGAGAGGCAAUGUGAAAGAGGGAGUAUUACUUUUAUGUACAAAGUUAUUUAUUUAUAGAAAUUUUGGUACAGUGUACAUUGAAAACCAUGUAAAAUAUUGAAGUGUCUAACAAAUGGCAUUGAAGUGUCUUUAAUAAAGGUUCAUUUAUAAAUGUCA